AGCGACAACGGCUCUGACCGUCUGGCAGGCCGCGUGGCGCCCGCGCCGGCCUUCCUGCAGGGGACUCCACCGGAGCCUUGCCAAUUCCGUUUGUUUCCCUGUUGUCGCCCGCUUCACCCUGGAUCAUGUUCAAGAAGUUUGAUGAAAAGGAAAGUGUGUCCAACUGCAUCCAGUUGAAAACGUCAGUUAUUAAGGGCAUUAAGAGCCAACUGGUAGAGCAAUUUCCAGGUAUUGAACCAUGGCUUAAUCAAAUCAUGCCUAAGAAAGAUCCUGUCAAAAUAGUCCGAUGCCACGAACAUACAGAAAUCCUUACCGUAAGUGGGGAAUUAUUGUUUUUUAGACAAAGAAAGGGGCCUUUUUGUCCAACUCUAAGGUUGCUUCACAAAUACCCUUUUAUCCUGCCACACCAGCAGGUUGAUAAAGGAGCUAUCAAAUUUGUACUCAGUGGCGCAAAUAUUAUGUGUCCAGGUUUAACUUCUCCUGGAGCUAAGCUGUACCCUGCUGCAGUAGAUACGAUUGUAGCAGUCACAGCGGAAGGAAAACAGCAUGCUCUGUGUGUUGGGGUCAUGAAGAUGUCUGCAGAAGAUAUUGAGAAAGUCAACAAAGGAAUUGGCAUUGAAAAUAUCCAUUAUUUAAAUGAUGGGCUGUGGCACAUGAAGACAUAUAAAUGAGCCUCAGAAGGAAUGCAUUUGGGGGGCUAAAU